AGACUGACCGCGGGGCAGCUGCGGAGCAUGUCGACCCCGGCCCGGAGGAGGCUCAUGCGGGAUUUCAAGCGGUUACAAGAGGACCCACCUGUGGGUGUCAGUGGCGCACCAUCUGAAAACAACAUCAUGCAGUGGAAUGCAGUUAUAUUUGGACCAGAAGGGACACCUUUUGAAGAUGGUACUUUUAAACUAGUAAUAGAAUUUUCUGAAGAAUAUCCAAAUAAACCACCAACUGUUAGGUUUUUAUCCAAAAUGUUUCAUCCAAAUGUGUAUGCUGAUGGUAGCAUAUGUUUAGAUAUCCUUCAGAAUCGAUGGAGUCCAACAUAUGAUGUAUCUUCUAUCUUAACAUCAAUUCAGUCUCUGCUGGAUGAACCGAAUCCUAACAGUCCAGCCAAUAGCCAGGCAGCACAGCUUUAUCAGGAAAACAAACGAGAAUAUGAGAAAAGAGUUUCGGCCAUUGUUGAACAAAGCUGGAAUGAUUCAUAAUAGACAACUGGUCUGUUAAUCUUUUUCAUCAUUGUUGUGUAUAAUUUACCUCUCAUUAGAAAGGCUAACAAAUUUUAAGUGCCACAGGUUUUAAGGAUUCUGCAGAAAAAAAAGAAAAAAGUCCUUCAGUUUAGAACCUACAAAAGCUUGUGUAUCUUGAUUAAUGUACUUUUUAUUGCAUGGUGUGAACUAAGUUAUUGCUGCAUAAAUUUGUAAUAUAUCCUGUUUGUAUUUUUUUCCAAGUGUAUAAUGUUGGUGUGGAGUUUUCAUGACAGAAUAUACACAUUUUGUAAAUCUGUACUUUUUUCAAAUAUUGAAUGCCUUAUUUUUGAAUUCUUUAGAUUUUUAAAUUGGAGAAAAGCACUUAAAGUUUUUUAUAUAUGAAUAUUACAUGUAAAGCUGUUAAAAUACAUAACUUCAGUGCAAGAGACUUUGUCACUUAUUUCCUUAUGUGUGUAGGAGGGGUUAAUAAGUCUCUAGCUCUCCAUCUAUUGAUAGUUUCAUUUACAAUUUCAAAAGAACAUUCUUAUAUUUUAUCAAGGAAGUCUUCAAAUUUGAUUCUAAAUAGCGAUUAUAAUCUCCAACUUUAUUUUGAAUGUACCUCUAUUAGUUUCAAUUGAGUAAUUCUAGACAUAACUGGUUUGACUCUGUCCAACUCUGUAUUUAGGCCAUUUGUUACAGUUUCUUCAUGCAUUACUUACUGUUAAAACUGUACCUUUUGCGAUUUCACAGUUGGCACUUCUGCCAUGAGCAGAGAACUGAUGCGACUUGUUUUGCUGCUUGGUAGCACUUUAAAAAAUUUUUUGAUUAAUGAAGAAAGUAAAACCAUAAACAUUUGCCAAAAAUUCAUGCCCCAGUAUUAGCAAUGAAUUAGUUGCAUUGGUUUGAGAAAGGCACAUAUUGGAGGGAAAUCUUGGUGUAACUUAAAUAUUUGAAAAUUACCUUUAAUGCAAUGCAUAUCUGUUUAUUCUGGGAAAUGUUUUAAUGCCAGGGCCUGCUGAGUUGCUUCUUCUUGUGGAGAUUUUUUUUUUAAUCUCCUGAGUUGUAUAAAAGUUGUACUGCAUCUUAGUUUACUGGAUAAAUUUAAAACACAGUAUUGUAGAAAGCUAAUACAAAACUAUCCUAUGCCUUCAAAUAGUAUAGAAAAUGGAAAAUAUACAAGUAAAUUCUGUUGAACCACCUGUGUAGUCUCUCUAGUAGUUAAAACAGCUAUUUUAGUAACCCCAAGAGUUUCUUCUCAUAUCCAUAAAAUUGGAUUACAGUAUGGCAAUAUCUACAGCUUCUAUUCAUUAUGCAACGUUUAACAUUGAUUGGAUAAAUGCUUAUAGGCUGGGCCAGGUGGCUCCCACCUGUAGUCCCAGCACUUUGGGAGGCAAAGGCGGGAGGAUCACUUGAGGCCAGGACUUUGAGACCAGCCAGGGCAACAUAAUAAGACUUUUCUCUACUUUAAAUUUUUUAAAAAAUUAGUUGGGCAUAGUGGCACUUGCCUGUAGUCUCAGCUACUUAGGAGGCUGAGGUGGCAGAAUAGCUUAUGCCUAGGAGGUUGAGGCUGCAGUGAGCUGUGAUUAUGCCAUUGCACUCCAGCCUGGGUGACAGAGCAAUACCCUGUCUUUAAAAAUAAAAGCUAUUACUUGGCAAAUUCUGAGGUAAGUGUAUGAUCUUAGGGAACUUUGAUACAAAUGGGAAUUCACUCACUGGAAUCGUGGCUCCCAAAAAGAUGCUUUAAUUGUGUGGUGCUUUUAUAGUUUAGCUCCA